UUGGCCUUCCAAAGUGAUGGGAUUACAGGCAGUAGCCACUGUGCCUAGCCAGAAACUCAACUUUUACUGGCUUACUCUUCAGGACCUCCCGCUCCUAUCAGAGCCUCCCUCCCCGACAACACCCCAGUUAUUUCAGGAGUGCCUUGGGGUCUCUUCAUGUUUAUAACUAAGUCUGCUCUGGCUGUUCCUUCCACUCCAUUUUGUGUCCAUGGGGCAGAGCAGUGCCCAACCAGUAGUCAUGAUUCCUCUGCUGGGCACCUCUGCUGCCCAGCCCUCUUGGGUUCGGAGUUCCACUGUGAUAUAUGGCAUAGUUGUUUGAGGAUGAGGGUGAGGUUGAAGUGAGUUCUCUCUCUCUUCUGCUUGUUGCAUUGGACGGAUCUGCCUUAUACCUCAAUGUUUCCAGACUUCAUUUUUAUUUACAACCCUUUUCUUCUCACCUCUGGGUGGUAGGAAGGUCUCCUGAAUCUAGUAUGGGUUGGUCAAACACAGCUACACUGAAAAUUACAUAUGUCUCUAAUGGCUAAGGCUUUCCUUUGGGGUGAAGUUCAUGGUCCCUAGCUCUCUAUGAGUUUAGAAUGGAUUUUCUCCCACCAAGCCGCUUAUAUUAAUGGAUAGUAGAGUUUGGCAGUAGGGCUUGGUGGAAUUUGAUGGGCUAUGCCGUGGGUUUACCAGAUGGACCCAGAUAUGCCUGGAACCCACAGUGGACACAGUUUGUGUCUCUUCUCAGAAGACUCUCCCUCAUUCUUGCUUCUUCAUGUGGUUCUUCUCUGUUGUCUUCCCAUCAAUGCAGAUUGCUCUAGUAUCGCCCAUCUUUAAAAAUUGCCCUUGAAACUACAUCCUCCCUCCGCUACUUCUCUAUCUCUUGACUCUCUAUCUCUUCACAUCCAAACCUCUCUAUUACAGCAUCCUGUUAUUUGCCUUCAUAAACAGCUUUCAUGACAAUAUAUAAUUAUCUAUGUAUUUGGGUGAUUAUUUAAUAUUUAUUCCUAAUUAAGCUUGAUAUCAUGGAUCAUGAAUGUUUAUUUUCCUUUUGCCAUUUUAUCUUCAAAUAUCUAGCACAGAGUUUAGUGCAGAAUAUGUGCUCACUGAAUAUUUGUUGCAAGCAUUGAAUAAAUGAAUAAAUGAAGGAAACAGGUUUCUGGUGGACGACUUUCCCAGCAGCCAAGUGCACCUGAAACUCACUUCUGUUUGAGCUAGGACAUUUGGGAGGUAGAAGACAUCGUAGAAGGAGUGAAAGAAGAAAAGAAGACUUAGAAACAUAGCUCAAAGUGAACACUGCUUCUCUUAGUUUCCUGGAUUUCUUCUGGACAUUUCCUCAAGAUGAAACUUCAGACACUUUGGAGUUUUUUUUGAAGACCACCAUAAAGAAAGUGCAUUUCAAUUGAAAAAUUUGGAUGGGAUCAAAAAUGAAUCUCAUUGAACAUUCCCAUUUACCUACCACAGAUGAAUUUUCUUUUUCUGAAAAUUUAUUUGGUGUUUUAACAGAACAAGUGGCAGGUCCUCUGGGACAGAACCUGGAAGUGGAACCAUACUCGCAAUACAGCAAUGUUCAGUUUCCCCAAGUUCAACCACAGAUUUCCUCGUCAUCCUAUUAUUCCAACCUGGGUUUCUACCCCCAGCAGCCUGAAGAGUGGUACUCUCCUGGAAUAUAUGAACUCAGGCGUAUGCCAGCUGAGACUCUCUACCAGGGAGAAACUGAGGUAGCAGAGAUGCCUGUAACAAAGAAGCCCCGCAUGGGCGCGUCAGCAGGGAGGAUCAAAGGGGAUGAGCUGUGUGUUGUUUGUGGAGACAGAGCCUCUGGAUACCACUAUAAUGCACUGACCUGUGAGGGGUGUAAAGGUUUCUUCAGGAGAAGCAUUACCAAAAACGCUGUGUACAAGUGUAAAAACGGGGGCAACUGUGUGAUGGAUAUGUACAUGCGAAGAAAGUGUCAAGAGUGUCGACUAAGGAAAUGCAAAGAGAUGGGAAUGUUGGCUGAAUGUAUGUAUACAGGCUUGUUAACUGAAAUUCAGUGUAAAUCUAAGCGACUGAGAAAAAAUGUGAAGCAGCAUGCAGAUCAGACCGUGAAUGAAGACAGUGAAGGUCGUGACUUGCGACAAGUGACCUCGACAACAAAGUCAUGCAGGGAGAAAACUGAACUCACCCCAGAUCAACAGACUCUUCUACAUUUUAUUAUGGAUUCAUAUAACAAACAGAGGAUGCCUCAGGAAAUAACAAAUAAAAUUUUAAAAGAAGAAUUCAGUGCAGAAGAAAAUUUUCUCAUUUUGACGGAAAUGGCAACCAAUCAUGUACAGGUUCUUGUAGAAUUCACAAAAAAGCUACCAGGAUUUCAGACUUUGGACCAUGAAGACCAGAUUGCUUUGCUGAAAGGGUCUGCGGUUGAAGCUAUGUUCCUUCGUUCAGCUGAGAUUUUCAAUAAGAAACUUCCGUCUGGGCAUUCUGACCUAUUGGAAGAAAGAAUUCGAAAUAGUGGUAUCUCUGAUGAAUAUAUAACACCUAUGUUUAGUUUUUAUAAAAGUAUUGGGGAACUGAAAAUGACUCAAGAGGAGUAUGCUCUGCUUACAGCAAUUGUUAUCCUGUCUCCAGAUAGACAAUACAUAAAGGAUAGAGAGGCAGUAGAGAAGCUUCAGGAGCCACUUCUUGAUGUGCUACAAAAGUUGUGUAAGAUUCACCAGCCUGAAAAUCCUCAACACUUUGCCUGUCUCCUGGGUCGCCUGACUGAAUUACGGACAUUCAAUCAUCACCACGCUGAGAUGCUGAUGUCAUGGAGAGUAAACGACCACAAGUUUACCCCACUUCUCUGUGAAAUCUGGGACGUGCAGUGAUGGGGAUUACAGGGGAGGGGUCUAGCUCCUUUUUCUCUCUCAUAUUAAUCUGAUGUAUAACUUUCCUUUAUUUCACUUGUACCCAGUUUCACUCAAGAAAUCUUGAUGAAUAUUUAUGUUGUAAUUACAUGUGUAACUUCCACAACUGUAAAUAUUGGGCUAGAUAGAACAACUUUCUCUACAUUGUGUUUUAAAAGGCUCCAGGGAAUCCUGCAUUCUAAUUGGCAAGCCCUGUUUGCCUAAUUAAAUUGAUUGUUACUUCAAUUCUAUCUGUUGAACUAGGGAAAAUCUCAUUUUGCUCAUCUUACCAUAUUGCAUAUAUUUUAUUAAAGAGUUGUAUUCAAUCUUGGCAAUAAAGCAAACAUAAUGGCAACAGGAUUUUCUUUGGGAACAAAAUUUGAUAAAUAUACAAACUCAUUUCUUUAAAUGUUGAAAGACAUCCUAUUGAAUCUGAGGGGGUAAUUUACAGAAAGAUACUGUCUCUCGCACUUUUGUCAUCUCUGGAAAAGUCCUGGUGAAUAGUCAUUCAUUUGUAAUAGCCCUCUGAUCAUUUCCUUUUCUUUGAAGUUCAAAGAGAAUAGCAAACAGAAAAGUUAACAAUUUUCACAUAAAAUAUUCCCUCAAGCAAUCCUUUCCCCCAUAGUUAGUCUUGAGGCAGGAUUCACAAAUUCAGAGUAUGCAGCUAACUGCAGUGAUGGGACCUUCGCUUUCCUCUCUUAAAAGUGAGGAAAUGAUUGGCUUCAUUGUAUCCAAUCAUCUUUCUGUUUUGUUUUGCUUUUGAAAACAUUCCUACAGCUGGGAGCACAGCUGCUGUAUACUUCCCCCAAAGCAGGAAUUAGUUCAUUUCCUUCCUUCAUUGUUACACUGUUGCAUUCUUCUCCCUAUUAUCCUUUGGUGAAUACAAUAAAACACCUUCUAUAAGUAA